CCCAGAGUGCUCUGCGCCGUGAAGAAGCGGCUCCCGGGGACUGGGGGCAUUUUGUGUUGGCUGGAGCUGGAGUAACAAGAUGGCGUCGUCCGCGGAGUGACAGGGGUCCCUCUGGGCCGGAGCCGGCGGCAGUGGUGGCAGCGGUAUCGCCGCCCUAGCUCACCGCGCCCCUUUUCCAGCCCGCGACGUCGCCGCGCAAGCGAGGCAGCGGCGGCCGCCGAGAAACAAGUGGCCCAGCCUGGUAACCGCCGAGAAGCCCUUCACAAACUGCGGCCUGGCAAAAAGAAACCUGACUGAGCGGCGGUGAUCAGGUUCCCCUCUGCUGAUUCUGGGCCCCGAACCCCGGUAAAGGCCUCCGUGUUCCGUUUCCUGCCGCCCUCCUCCGUAGCCUUGCCUAGUGUAGGAGCCCCGAGGCCUCCGUCCUCUUCCCAGAGGUGUCGGGGCUUGGCCCCAGCCUCCAUCUUCGUCUCUCAGGAUGGCGAGUAGCAGCGGCUCCAAGGCUGAAUUCAUUGUCGGAGGGAAAUAUAAACUGGUACGGAAGAUCGGGUCUGGCUCCUUCGGGGACAUCUAUUUGGCGAUCAACAUCACCAACGGCGAGGAAGUGGCAGUGAAGCUAGAAUCUCAGAAGGCCAGGCAUCCCCAGUUGCUGUACGAGAGCAAGCUCUAUAAGAUUCUUCAAGGUGGGGUUGGCAUCCCCCACAUACGGUGGUAUGGUCAGGAAAAAGACUACAAUGUACUAGUCAUGGAUCUUCUGGGACCUAGCCUCGAAGACCUCUUCAAUUUCUGUUCAAGAAGGUUCACAAUGAAAACUGUACUUAUGUUAGCUGACCAGAUGAUCAGUAGAAUUGAAUAUGUGCAUACAAAGAAUUUUAUACACAGAGACAUUAAACCAGAUAACUUCCUAAUGGGUAUUGGGCGUCACUGUAAUAAGUGUUUAGAAUCUCCAGUGGGGAAGAGGAAAAGAAGCAUGACUGUUAGUACUUCUCAGGACCCAUCUUUCUCAGGAUUAAACCAGUUAUUCCUUAUUGAUUUUGGUUUGGCCAAAAAGUACAGAGACAACAGGACAAGGCAACACAUACCAUACAGAGAAGAUAAAAACCUCACUGGCACUGCCCGAUAUGCUAGCAUCAAUGCACAUCUUGGUAUUGAGCAGAGUCGCCGAGAUGACAUGGAAUCAUUAGGAUAUGUUUUGAUGUAUUUUAAUAGAACCAGCCUGCCAUGGCAAGGGCUAAAGGCUGCAACAAAGAAACAAAAAUAUGAAAAGAUUAGUGAAAAGAAGAUGUCCACGCCUGUUGAAGUUUUAUGUAAGGGGUUUCCUGCAGAAUUUGCGAUGUACUUAAACUAUUGUCGUGGGCUACGCUUUGAGGAAGCCCCAGAUUACAUGUAUCUGAGGCAGCUAUUCCGCAUUCUUUUCAGGACCCUGAACCAUCAAUAUGACUACACAUUUGAUUGGACAAUGUUAAAGCAGAAAGCAGCACAGCAGGCAGCCUCUUCCAGUGGGCAGGGUCAGCAGGCCCAAACCCCCACAGGCAAGCAAACUGACAAAACCAAGAGUAACAUGAAAGGUUUCUAAGCAUGAAUUGAGGAACAGAAGAAGCAGAGCAGAUGAUCGGAGCAGCAUUUGUUUCUCCCCAAAUCUAGAAAUUUUAGUUCAUAUGUACACUAGCCAGUGGUUGUGGACAACCAUUUACUUGGUGUAAAGAACUUAAUUUCAGUAUAAACUGACUCUGGGCAGCAUUGGUGAUGCUGUAUCCUGAGUUGUAGCCUCUGUAAUUGUGAAUAUUAACUGAGAUAGUGAAACAUGGUGUCCGGUUUUCUAUUGCAUUUUUUCAAGUGGAAAAGUUAACUAAAUGGUUGACACACAAAAAUUGGUGGAGAAAUUGUGCAUAUGCCAAUUUUUUGUUAAAACCUUUUGUUUUGAACUAUACUGCUUUGAGAUCUCAUUUCAGAAGAACGGCAUGAACAGUCUUCAGCCACAGUUGUGAUGGUUGUUAAAUGCUCACAAUUGUGCAUUCUUAGGGUUUUUCCAUCCCUGGGGUUUGCAAGUUGUUCACUUAAAACAUUCUUAAAAUGGUUGGCUUCUUGUCUGCAAGCCAGCUGAUAUGGUAGCAACCAAAGAUUCCAGUGUUUGAGCAUAUGAAAGACUCUGCCUGCUUAAUUGUGCUAGAAAUAACAGCAUCUAAAGUGAAGACUUAAGAAAAACUUAGUGACUACUAGAUUAUCCUUAGGACUCUGCAUUAACUCUAUAAUGUUCUUGGUAUUAAAAAAAAAGCAUAUUUGUCACAGAAAUUUAGUUAACAUCUUACAACUGAACAUGUAUGUAUGUUGCUUAGAUAAAUGUAAUCACUGUAAACAUCUAUAUGAUCUGGGAUUUUGUUUUUAUUUUGAAAUGGGAGCUUUUUUGUUUACAAGUUCAUUAAAAACUAAAAACUGUUUCUGUAAGGAAAUGAGAUUUUUUUUAAACAACAAAAAAUGCCUUGCUGACUCACUAUUAAAUAAAAAUCUCCCCAAUUUUUUGAUAGACUACUUCAAGCCAUUUGUUACAUGGUAUUCCUUUGCAAGUCAAUUUAGGUUUCGUGUUAUAACUUUUCCUCUUUUUUUAAGAAAAAUGAAAAAAGUAAUUCUUUUGUCUGAAGGGGAAAGGCAUUCUUUCAUUUUUUUCUUUUUUUUUUUUUUUUUUUAUGACUUGCAGGCACAAUAUCUAGUACUGCAACUGCCAGAACUUGGUAUUGUAGCUGCUGCCCGCUGACUAGCAGCUGGACUGAUUUUGAAUAAAAAUGAAAGCAUUAAAGGGUUUCCCUACAAAACAUUUUUCUUUAAAAUACUUUUGAAAUGGCUAUAAGCAGUUGACUUUCACCCUUGGAGAGCAUCACACUGUGUGAGGUUCAGUGAUUGUUGACCCUCCCCAGCCCCUCCUGCUUCUUUAAGUUAUCUGUGUGCGUGCGCUUCCUCUCAAUCUUCUUUGCACGCUCAUUUCUUUUUCUCUGACCCAUGAGAAAGGAAAACUUACUGAUGAUAAUUUUUAAAUAGUGUAAUUUAUUCAUUUAUAGCAUGUCAGGAUAAAUUAAAAGAACAUUUGUCUGGAAAUGCUGCCGGGAGCCUAUUGUGUAAAUGUAGGUAUUUUGUAAAAUAACCUUGAAAUUGUAAAUUGACACGUGUUUGGUCAGAUUGUGUCAAGUUUAAUUUGUUUUGUUUUCUUUUUUCUUUUUUUUAUUUGAAAACUACUUUAGCAAUAAUUAAUUCCAUGAUUAUCACAUUCUGCCAUUAAGGGAUAUUAGUACCGUAAUACUGAAGAAAUUUUAUUAAGUCUGAACUUCUGGGGUAGGCAGCUUCUUUGUUUCUUUUCUAUCCACCCUUGUCGGUUGAGGUAUUUGUUUCUUGACUAAUAAACCCUUUGAUACUUUUAGCCAGAAAUCAGUCUCAUAAAGCUAUUUUUGAGUAUAGUUUGUGUAAAAUAAAAAUGUUUAGCUUUGGUAAUAACUUCCAAGCUGAACUCCCUCUAGCAAGAUAUUUUUCAGUGCUUUUAUUUACUAUGCACUUAGACUAUGCACUUUUUCUGAAAUAUUUUUGUAACACUUUUUUGUAUUUUUGCCAUUUGAAAAGGUUGUGGUGUAGUUGGUCUGUAAUUAAGUUGCAGAUUUAAAACUGCUGUUAGCUUUGUAAAUCAAAAUAUAGGUGUUUUUUGUCCUGGUAUAUCGUCAUUCCAUCUGCAGCUGGAGCUGGAAUCCCAUUGAUCUUCUAGCUACCAUUCAUUUUCUUCACUGUUCACAAAAGAAGAGUGUGAAAUUCAGUGAAUGCUGUUACUAAUCCUGUUACGAGAUGAAUCUCAUUUCACCAAAAUUAAAUUAUGUUUUUCCGCUAAAAUGAUGAUACAAGUUGAAGACACAUCACUCUGAAAUUGGAAGACCUCACCACUUAAGGCUCCACAGUGGCUUACUCAGCUGAACUCUAGGUUACUACUCUUUACUUUGUUCACCCAUUGGGGGGUGCAGUUUUUUUAAAAUGUUGGGAGAUGGCCAUUCUAACUACUGUUGAAUGUCUCUGUUUUGGGAAGGUAUAACAAGAAAUAAAAAAGAAUAUAUAUGAAGGGAGAGACUGGUUAUCUCCUCCCAUAUGGUUGUGCUUAUCCUCUUAUGGCUUACAAAUGAAUAUUUGGAGGUUUGCUUUCACAAUGAUUUCCCAUCAACAAAUAUUUUUAGUAGGAUUUUUCCUGUUUCUGUUAGUCCUUGCAGUACUCAUAAAUGUUUUAAGCUGAGCAUACUGUAAUAGUCAUAAGUUUAAUUUCAUUAUAAUAAAAAUAAUCAAACAAAAGGACUUUAGAACCCAAGACAAUGAGCUAGUUUUCCCUAAAGUUUGCUGAACUAUUAAGGAAUAUGUUCUUAUAGCUUUUGACUAGAAUGAGUCAUGGGAAUUCUAAGAAGGGAUGGCCUAGACAUUUUUAGCUCAGUUAAAUUCAGCAUUUAAUGCAGGUGAGUUCCUGGGUCGUUUUCCAACUAGUCUGGAACAGUCUGGUUCUGACUCAAACUGGUAUAAAGCAUUAUUUUAGGUUUUCUCUUUGCCAGUUUUUAAGCAGUUAUAACCAUGUAAAUCAAGAUGUGAGGACAUCUAUAUGAAGUAUAGUAAAGAAGUGGUGUCAGCAGAUCAAUAUGUGUGUCCUGGGUGUGCUGCUCUCUUAAGUGAGACUUUGUGAGACUAUACUUUAAAUGCAUUAUUACCAUUGCUUACAUUUUGGGGGAUUUUCUUCCUCCUCAAAACUUCCAUUUCUAUUGUAAUAUUCUUAAUGACAAUCUUUUUUUUUUUUUAGCAGUGUAUGUUUGAAACAGCCAAAGAUGGCGAUGAACCAAGUGUAAAUUGAUCUAAGCAGCCCAUGCAGUUUGUGUUGAAUCAACAAACAGUGUAUUGUUGAAGUGAAAUUAUUUUCUGAAAUGACUUGUUAGACCAGUUUUGAGGACAUACUCAAAAGUAGAGUAAUAAUGGCUCCUGGGAUGGAGAAAUAUGAGAUGAACCUGGAACAUUCUAUUAUGGUGCCACAAAGGAAAUCUAAAAAAAAAAAAAAAAAAAAAAGUGGUUGGCUAGGAGCAGUGGCACACGCCUGUGAUUCCAGCACUUUGGGAGGCCGAAGUGGGCAGGAGUUCAAGACCAGCCUGGCCAACAUAGUGAAACCCUGUCUCUACUAAAAAUACAAAAAUUAGCCGGGUGUGGUGGCGGGCGCCUGUAAUCCCAGCUUUUCAAGAGGCUGAGGCAGAAGAAUCGCUUGAACCCGGGAGAUGGAGGUUGCAGUGAGCUGAGAUCGUGCCACUGCACUCCAGCCUGGGCGUUGCAGUGAGACUCCGUCUCAACAACAACAAAAAGGUGGAUACAUGUCAAAAGGGCACAGGAGCCACUUGAAGGAUUAUACUUGCUAAAUCUGUGUCAAUUAUCAAAAUAAACUGGUAGCAACGUUA